AGGGAGGGCUCGGCCUUGGCUCCACACUGCGCUGCCCAGAGGCCCCGCUGACUCCUGCCAGCCUCCAGGUCCCCGUGGUACCAAAGCUGAACAUGGACGUGACCAUCCAGCACCCCUGGUUCAAGCGCACCCUGGGGCCCUUCUACCCCAGCCGGCUGUUCGACCAGUUUUUCGGCGAGGGCCUUUUUGAGUAUGACCUGCUGCCCUUCCUGUCGUCCACCAUCAGCCCCUACUACCGCCAGUCCCUCUUCCGCACCGUGCUGGACUCCGGCAUCUCUGAGGUUCGAUCCGACCGGGACAAGUUCGUCAUCUUCCUCGAUGUGAAGCACUUCUCCCCGGAGGACCUCACCGUGAAGGUGCAGGACGACUUUGUGGAGAUCCACGGAAAGCACAACGAGCGCCAGGACGACCACGGCUACAUUUCCCGUGAGUUCCACCGCCGCUACCGCCUGCCGUCCAACGUGGACCAGUCGGCCCUCUCUUGCUCCCUGUCUGCCGAUGGCAUGCUGACCUUCUGUGGCCCCAAGAUCCAGACUGGCCUGGAUGCCACCCACGCCGAGCGAGCCAUCCCCGUGUCGCGGGAGGAGAAGCCCACCUCGGCUCCCUCGUCCUAAGCAGGCAUUGCCUCGGCUGGCUCCCCUGCAGCCCUGGCCCAUCAUGGGGGGAGCACCCUGAGGGCGGGGUGUCUGUCUUCCUUUGCUUCCCUUUUUUCCUUUCCACCUUCUCACAUGGAAUGAGGGUUUGAGAGAGCAGCCAGGAGAGCUUAGGGUCUCAGGGUGUCCCAGACCCCGACACCGGCCAGUGGCGGAAGUGACCGCACCUCACACUCCUUUAGAUAGCAGCCUGGCUCCCCUGGGGUGCAGGCGCCUCAACUCUGCUGAGGGUCCAGAAGGAGGGGGUGACCUCCGGCCAGGUGCCUCCUGACACACCUGCAGCCUCCCUCCGCGGCGGGCCCUGCCCACACCUCCUGGGGCGCGUGAGGCCCGUGGGGCCGGGGCUUCUGUGCACCUGGGCUCUCGCGGCCUCUUCUCUCAGACCGUCUUCCUCCAACCCCUCUAUGUAGUGCCGCUCUUGGGGACAUGGGUCGCCCAUGAGAGCGCAGCCCGCGGCAAUCAAUAAACAGCAGGUGAUACAAGCAA